CCCGCCAUCUCUCAGCACCUCCUCGGCAGCCCCUCGGCUCCUUCUCGGUCACGCGCCUGCCCCAACCUCUGGCUGGCUUCGGAGCCUGCAGGCACUGAAGGGAGUGCAGGGUGUGGAUCGCUGCCCCAGCCCGGGCCGCCGCCUCCGAGCAGUCGGCACCCGGAGGCAGGAGGCACAAUGCAGGCGUGCGGGGGCGGCGCGGCCGGCCGUCGGGCCUUCGACAGCAUCUGCCCCAACAGAAUGCUGGCACUGCCGGGCCGGGCGCUGCUCUGCAAGCCGGGGAAGCCGGAGAGGAAGUUCGCUCCUCCGCGGAAGUUCUUCCCCGGAUGCACAGGCGGGAGCCCGGUGUCGGUGUACGAGGAUCCCCCGGACGCCGAGCCCACAGCGCUGCCAGCCCUCACCACCAUAGACCUGCAGGACCUCGCUGACUGCUCUUCGCUACUCGGGUCCGACGCGCCGCCUGGUGGUGACCUGGCCGCCUCGCAGAACCAUUCCCACCAAACGGAAGCAGACUUCAAUCUGCAAGAUUUCAGAGACACGGUGGAUGAUCUCAUUUCAGACUCAUCCUCUAUGAUGUCGCCUACCCUGGCCAGCGGAGACUUCCCCUUCUCUCCUUGCGACAUAUCACCAUUCGGGCCCUGCCUCUCCCCGCCACUGGACCCACGGGCCCUGCAGUCACCACCGCUGCGCCCUCCAGACGUGCCCCCGCCUGAGCAAUACUGGAAGGAGGUGGCGGACCAGAACCAGAGAGCGUUGGGAGACGCGCUUGUUGAGAAUAAUCAACUGCACGUGACAUUGACCCAGAAACAGGAGGAGAUCGCCUCGCUCAAGGAGCGGAACGUGCAGCUGAAGGAACUCGCCAGCCGAACCCGGCACCUGGCCUCGGUGCUGGAUAAGCUGAUGAUCACACAGUCCCGGGAUUGUGGGGCGGCGGCCGAGCCCUUCCUGCUCAAGGCGAAGGCCAAAAGGAGCCUGGAGGAGUUGGUCAGCGCUGCGGGGCAGGAUUGCGCGGAAGUGGACGCCAUCCUGAGGGAGAUUUCCGAGCGCUGCGAUGAAGCCCUUCAGAGCCGCGAUCCCAAGCGGCCCCGACUGCUGCCAGAGCCCGCGAAUACUGACACCAGGCCCGGGAACCUGCAUGGCGCCUUCCGGGGGCUGCGCACAGACUGCAGCCGGAGCGCGUUGAACCUGAGCCACAGUGAGCUGGAGGAGGGCGGCUCCUUCAGCACCCGCAUCCGCAGCCACAGCACCAUCCGCACCCUCGCCUUCCCCCAGGGCAAUGCCUUCACCAUCAGAACAGCCAACGGGGGUUACAAGUUCCGCUGGGUCCCCAGUUGAGCUGUGAUGUGGUCCCCCAAAACACUGCCCUGUGUUUCCACUGAAGUGCCUGGGGGCUUCCCAGAACUUUGCCUUCAGGUUGAAUGCCACCCUGAAACACUUUUUCAGGAACAAAAGCAUCUUGAUACCGAUGCAUUGUAAAUUUCUGCUACAAAACAUUGUAUAGCCCCUCCCCUUGUCACAGUGAAACUCUGUUUAUAUAUGUAUAUGUCACAUAUGUCACAGCCAAUUUUAAAAGUAUUUAUUUUUAGCAGCUUUGAAUUAUGUAUUUUUAGAGCAGGGAAGGAUUUAGAAACCAUAGUUACUUUUAUAAUUAUGUAAUGCUCUAAUAUUAUAAGAAGGAAAAGAAGGCUCUAAGAGAUUAAGUAAUUUCCUGCAAUGGGAAACACUGGAACCUUUCAAUCACUUUAACUAGUCACUUAAGGACUCUAGGCCCAGAAGCCUGGUUUCUGGGUGAAUGUUUUUAUACAUCACUCAACUUCCCUCGUCCUAAAAGGACACCUAAUUUUGUUACUAUUGAAAAUUUUUAUUUUGGUGGCCAGAAUACGAAAUCGGGAGAGGUAACCCAAACAGUUGUCUUAGGAAAAGGCAGAUUCUCAGAGGCAAUGGGCUAUCAACAAAAUAGGUGCUAAGCACAUUUGUUUGUAAUGAUCAUUCAUAUAAUUUAGAAGAUUUAUGGUAACAGUUUAUAUUCAUUAUCCAUACAGUUCUAUUUGUGCAAAUAGAAUAACCACCUAUAAGCAAACAGUGUUAAUGAGAAAUAUAUAUUGUUUUAAGAAAAUAGCAUAUACCGCAUGAAAAA